AGCAGACCCUGAAAGCUGAGCUGCCCUGACCCCCAAAGUGAGGAGAAGCUGCAAGGGAAAAGGGAGGGACAGAUCAGGGAGACCGGGGAAGAAGGAGGAGCAGCCAAGGAGGCUGCUGUCCCCCCACAGAGCAGCUCGGACUCAGCUCCCGGAGCAACCCAGCUGCGGAGGCAACGGCAGUGCUGCUCCUCCAGCGAAGGACAGCAGGCAGGCAGACAGACAGAGGUCCUGGGACUGGAAGGCCUCAGCCCCCAGCCACUGGGCUGGGCCUGGCCCAAUGGCCUUUAAUGACCUCCUGCAGCAGGUGGGGGGUGUCGGCCGCUUCCAGCAGAUCCAGGUCACCCUGGUGGUCCUCCCCCUGCUCCUGAUGGCUUCUCACAACACCCUGCAGAACUUCACUGCUGCCAUCCCUACCCACCACUGCCGCCCGCCUGCCGAUGCCAACCUCAGCAAGAACGGGGGGCUGGAGGUCUGGCUGCCCCGGGACAGGCAGGGGCAGCCUGAGUCCUGCCUCCGCUUCACCUCCCCGCAGUGGGGACUGCCCUUUCUCAAUGGCACAGAAGCCAAUGGCACAGGGGCCACAGAGCCCUGCACCGAUGGCUGGAUCUAUGACAACAGCACCUUCCCAUCUACCAUCGUGACUGAGUGGGACCUUGUGUGCUCUCACAGGGCCCUACGCCAGCUGGCCCAGUCCUUGUACAUGGUGGGGGUGCUGCUCGGAGCCAUGGUGUUCGGCUACCUUGCAGACAGGCUAGGCCGCCGGAAGGUACUCAUCUUGAACUACCUGCAGACAGCUGUGUCAGGGACCUGCGCAGCCUUCGCACCCAACUUCCCCAUCUACUGCGCCUUCCGGCUCCUCUCGGGCAUGGCUCUGGCUGGCAUCUCCCUCAACUGCAUGACACUGAAUGUGGAGUGGAUGCCCAUUCACACACGGGCCUGCGUGGGCACCUUGAUUGGCUAUGUCUACAGCCUGGGCCAGUUCCUCCUGGCUGGUGUGGCCUACGCUGUGCCCCACUGGCGCCACCUGCAGCUACUGGUCUCUGCGCCUUUUUUUGCCUUCUUCAUCUACUCCUGGUUCUUCAUUGAGUCGGCCCGCUGGCACUCCUCCUCCGGGAGGCUGGACCUCACCCUGAGGGCCCUGCAGAGAGUCGCCCGGAUCAAUGGGAAGCGGGAAGAAGGAGCCAAAUUGAGUAUGGAGGUACUCCGGGCCAGUCUGCAGAAGGAGCUGACCAUGGGCAAAGGCCAGGCAUCGGCCAUGGAGCUGCUGCGCUGCCCCACCCUCCGCCACCUCUUCCUCUGCCUCUCCAUGCUGUGGUUUGCCACUAGCUUUGCAUACUAUGGGCUGGUCAUGGACCUGCAGGGCUUUGGAGUCAGCAUCUACCUAAUCCAGGUGAUCUUUGGUGCUGUGGACCUGCCUGCCAAGCUUGUGGGCUUCCUUGUCAUCAACUCCCUGGGUCGCCGGCCUGCCCAGAUGGCUGCACUGCUGCUGGCAGGCAUCUGCAUCCUGCUCAAUGGGGUGAUACCCCAGGACCAGUCCAUUGUCCGAACCUCUCUUGCUGUGCUGGGGAAGGGUUGUCUGGCUGCCUCCUUCAACUGCAUCUUCCUGUAUACUGGGGAACUGUAUCCCACAAUGAUCCGGCAGACAGGCAUGGGAAUGGGCAGCACCAUGGCCCGAGUGGGCAGCAUCGUGAGCCCACUGGUGAGCAUGACUGCCGAGCUCUACCCCUCCAUGCCUCUCUUCAUCUACGGUGCUGUUCCUGUGGCCGCCAGCGCUGUCACUGUCCUCCUGCCAGAGACCCUGGGCCAGCCACUGCCAGACACGGUGCAGGACCUGGAGAGCAGGUGGGCCCCCACUCAGAAAGAAGCAGGGAUAUAUCCCAGGAAAGGGAAACAGACGCGACAGCAACAAGAGCACCAGAAGUAUAUGGUCCCACUGCAGGCCUCAGCACAAGAGAAGAAUGGACUCUGAGGACUGAGAAGGGGCCUUACAGAACCCUAAAGGGAGGGAAGGUCCUACAGGUCUCCGGCCACCCACACAAGGAGGAGGAAGAGGAAAUGGUGACCCAAGUGUGGGGGUUGUGGUUCAGGAAAGCAUCUUCCCAGGGGUCCACCUCCCUUUAUAAACCCCACCAGAACCACAUCAUUAAAAGGUUUGACUGCGCACCA